CUCUUUUCCGUGGCGCCUCGGAGGCGUUCAGCUGCUUCAAGAUGAAGCUGAACAUCUCCUUCCCAGCCACUGGCUGCCAGAAACUCAUUGAAGUGGACGAUGAACGCAAACUUCGUACUUUCUAUGAGAAGCGUAUGGCCACAGAAGUUGCUGCUGACGCUCUGGGUGAAGAAUGGAAGGGUUAUGUGGUCCGAAUCAGUGGUGGGAACGACAAACAAGGUUUCCCCAUGAAGCAGGGUGUCUUGACCCAUGGCCGUGUCCGCCUGCUACUGAGUAAGGGGCAUUCCUGUUACAGACCAAGGAGAACUGGAGAAAGAAAGAGAAAAUCAGUUCGUGGUUGCAUUGUGGAUGCAAAUCUGAGCGUUCUCAACUUGGUUAUUGUAAAAAAAGGAGAGAAGGAUAUUCCUGGACUGACUGAUACUACAGUGCCUCGCCGCCUGGGCCCCAAAAGAGCUAGCAGAAUCCGCAAACUUUUCAAUCUCUCUAAAGAAGAUGAUGUCCGCCAGUAUGUUGUAAGAAAGCCCUUAAAUAAAGAAGGUAAGAAACCUAGGACCAAAGCACCCAAGAUUCAGCGUCUUGUUACUCCACGUGUCCUGCAGCACAAACGGCGGCGUAUUGCUCUGAAGAAGCAGCGUACCAAGAAAAAUAAAGAAGAGGCUGCAGAAUAUGCUAAACUUUUGGCCAAGAGAAUGAAGGAGGCUAAGGAGAAGCGCCAGGAACAAAUUGCGAAGAGACGCAGACUUUCCUCUCUGCGAGCUUCUACUUCUAAGUCUGAAUCCAGUCAGAAAUAAGAUUUUUUGAGUAACAAAUAAAUAAGAUCAGACUCUGAUCUCUGUUGACUUUUCAUUGCUGAUAGAAAACUACAUAAAUGAAGAGAGGGAAAGUUAGGUCAUAGAAAAUGGGGAUAUGUAUAUAUGGUAUUCCAAUGGUGGAUAAAGUCAGACCUAUUGUGUGUGGUAGUGGAAGACAAGGUCAGUGUACAGGGGUUCCUUUCAGGGGAUGGGUGGCACAGGAAGGGAUUCUGAGCAUAAGACACCUGCCUCUUCAGAAUGGCAUGGAACUUAGGGGAAAUGAUGAGGACUAUUAAUCUUUUUUAUAUAGUUUAUUUUUGAGGAAUAUAGCUCUUUAAAGCACUAUACACAAUUUAAUACAUGAAAAUUGACCUUGUGAAGAUGAACAUGUCUUUUUUAAAAGGUAACUUUUAAGGCAUAGUUUUAGUGGAUACCUAGUUUUAGUGGAUACCAUCCACUAAAUGGUUUUUAAGCCAUUUCAAAUUUGUUUUAACAAAGCUUUUCAACUCCAGUGAAUUGUUAGGCUGUUCACACACUGAAAAGGAAAUGACUAAAAACAUUCUUGGAUCAGUGAAAAA